AGAGGGCUCUUCCGGCGCCUUCCCAGGCGGGGAUGCUGCGGCUCCGCAGCGGGCUGAGGCACCUUCGGGCAACACCCAAUACUCGGGGCUCCGCUCGGCUUCUUUGCGCCGAGAUGCCUAAGAAGGCUGGUGCGACGACCAAGGGUAAAAGCCAGAGCAAGGAACCAGAGAGACCACUUCCUCCCUUAGGUCCUGUGGCAGUUGAUCCUAAAGGAUGCGUCACCAUAGCCAUCCAUGCAAAACCUGGCUCCAAACAAAAUGCUGUAACAGAUUUGACAGCAGAGGCUGUAAAUGUAGCUAUUGCAGCACCUCCAUCAGAGGGAGAGGCUAAUGCUGAGCUCUGUCGGUAUCUUUCCAAGGUCCUAGAACUCAGGAAGAGUGAUGUGGUUUUGGAUAAGGGUGGUAAAUCUCGUGAAAAGGUGGUGAAGCUUUUGGCUUCUACAACUCCAGAAGAGAUCUUGGAGAAAUUAAAAAAGGAAGCCAAAAAAACAUAAAAGCAAGAAAUGAGGCCGGGCGCAGUGGCUCAUGCCUGUAAUCCCAGCACUUUGGGAGGCCGUGGUGGGCGGAUCACCUGAGGUCAGGAGUUCGAGACCAGCCUGACCAACAUGGUGAAACCCCAUCUCUACGAAAAAUACAAAAUUAGCCAGAUGUGAUGGCGCAUGCCUGUAAUCCCAGUUACUCAGGAGGCUGAGGCAGGAGAAUCACUUGAACCUGGGGGGCGGAGGUUGCAGUAAGCCGAGAUCGCGCCGUUGCACUCCAGCCUGGGCAACAAGAGUGAAACUCUCUCCCCCCGAAAAAAAAGAAAUAAAAAAUACAUCCUUGAGAAACUUUUUUAUUGCUAAUGGUGAAGAGGCUGUUAAAUAGAAAAAUAUACUACAUGCACAGAAGAACAUGGGGGACAUAUAUAUAUGUAUAUAUUCGAAUAAGACUCCAAAAAGUAGAAAUUUAAAAAGUGCUAUACAUUGCAUCAGGUUCUAAAAUCCCAAACCCCAAACAGCCUGGAACAUGUUACUCUGAUUUCAUGGCGUUGUAAAAUAACAGAGCUGGGAAGAAUAUUCAAGAUGACCUGAUUUAACACCUUUCAUUCUGUUGGGGGGCCUUUGAUUUCCUAUAUCCAGAAGUUGAGAGACUUACUCAAGAUUGUACCAUGCAAGCUGGCAACUAGAACCCAAAUCCUUGGACUACUUGUUGAAUGCAGUUUUUCUAGAUUGUAAAUUAAAAAUCAUAUCUCCACAACGGUUCUGGAAUUCUGGGGAUUGCCUUCUAAUCCAGUUUACAAGUGACAGAAAACCUGUUAUGCUGCUUUGUAGUCUUACCUUAGAUUUUUAAAUGCUUAUUUAAAUGUAAAAAAAAUUUUUUUUUUACAUCUUUUAAAGACUAUAUUUACCAUUUUGUUGAAAAAGUAAAGAAAAAUCAUGACUUGUAAUUAAAUGUGAAUUAUAAUUUUUGAGAAGUCACUGAAUUUUCAUCUUCCUCUAAUAACUUAAAUAAUCAGCAAAUUCAGUAGUUUUUAUGAAUCUCCAAAGAUCCUUAAAAGAAGAAAGAGGACUUGGAAGCUAUUUUCAGUAUUUGUAAAAGCUUGUCAGAAAUUACAUCUAUAUUAAAGUUUCAAAAGCUAAUAAUAUAUUUUUACAUCUUCAGGUCAAGUUAUAGUAAUUUAUUAAAGAAAAUAAAAUUAAUUUCCUUUGCUGAUCAGGAGAGCUGAUCUGCAGUUGUGCGCUUUGUCCAGCAAGUACAUGAGAAAGAUGUAUUGAUGGACCAAAUCAUUAAAAACAAAAUCCACAAGGAAGAACAAUAAUAAAAAUUGCUGAUGGUAGCUGGGCUUGGUGGCUCACGCCUGUAAUCCCAGCGCUUUGGAAGGUUGAGGCAGGAGGAACACUUGAGCCCAGGAGUUUGAGACCAGCCUGGGCAACGAAGUGAGACCCUGUAUCUGUCUCUGUCUCUUUCUUUAUAGAUAGAUAGAUAUACAUAGAUAGAUUUUAUACAUAGAUAUAUAUAUUUAUAUGUAAGAUUAUAUAUAAGACCUCAUAUAUAAGAAGUCCAGGCCGGGUGUGGUGGCUCAUGCCUGUAAUCCCAGCACUUUGGGAGGUCGAGGCGGGUGGAUCACCUGAGGUUAGGAGUUUGAGACCAGCCCGGCCAACAUAGUAAAACCCCAUCUCUACUAAAAAUAUAAAAACUAGCCAGGCAUGGUGGUGGGUGCCUGUAAUCUCAGCUACUCGGGAGGCUGAGGCAGGAGAAUUGCUUGAACCCAGGAGACGGAAGUUGCAGUGAGCCCACACGGUGCCACUGCACUCCAGCCUCGGCGACAAGAGUGAGACUCCGUCUCAAAAAGAAAGAAAAAAUCCCAGACAGUGAAAGAGAAGCUACUCGUCUAGUACAACUCUUAACUUGUACCAAAUAGGUAUCAAGGGCAAGAAAAGGUGGCUUAUGUGAGAUCACAGUGCACAUUAAUGGCAGAGCUUGGUUUAAGCCCAGCUGCUUUGUCUUCUAAACUGUGCCAUAUACUGCCUGCAAAUGUGCUUCUGUUUUACAUGGUCUUAAGAGCUUUUCCCACUCUUUCUCAAGACCAUUGCCAUGUGUGCUGUAAAGCCGUUUUACUUGUGGAUUUUACAUGGAUCACUGUUAGAAUGUCAUAAAAUGAUAUCAUAAAAGAUCAACUUUCCUGGCCGGGCAUGGUAGCUCACACCUGUAAUCCCAGCACUUUGGGAGGCCAAGGCAGGUGGAUCACCUGAGGUCGGGAAUUCGAGACCAGCCUGACCAACAUGGAGAAACCCCAUCUCUACUAAAAAUACAAAAAAUUAGCUGGGCGUGGUGGCACAUGCCUGUAAUUGCAGCUACUCGGGAGGCUGAGGUAGGAGAAUCGCUUGAACCCGGGAGUUGGAGGUUGCGGUGAGCUGAGAUCGUGCCAUUGCACUCUAGCCUGGGCAAAAGGAGCGAAACUCCAUCUCAAAAAAAAAAAAAAAAAAAAAGGAUCAACUUUUGGUCAGGCGUGUUGGCUUACGCCUGUAAUUCCAGCGCUUUGGGAGGCCGAGGCAGGCAGAUCACGAGGUCAGGAGUUCAAGAUCACCCUGGCCAACAUGGUGAAACCCCGUCUCUACUAAAAAUACAAAAGUUACCUGGGCAUAGUGGCAGAUGCUUGUAAUCCCAGCUACUCGGGAGGCUGAGGCAGGAGAAUUGCUUGUGAACCGGGACCCUGGAGGCAGAGGUUGCAGUGAGCCAAGAUCGCACAACUGCGAACUGCGCUCCAGCGUGGGCUGCAGAGGCAGACUCCGUCUCAAGAAAAAAAAAAAUCAGCUUUCUUUCCUUCCCCUGAAUCUUCUGCAGUGCCAGUUUCAUCCUCAGGCCCACUUGUUUCAUGUAGACAAAAGGCCAACCAGGUUUCAUAUUCACGUAUCAACCCCUGCAGUAGGAGAAAAGGCCACUCCUAGGAGCUCUGGUAUUUUCCAGAAGCUUUCAGUCAGCCUUCCCUUGUAUCAGCCCAAAUCAAGUCACAUGAAAUUUCUAAGCCAGCCCCUGUGAUCAGGGAAUGCCAUUCUAUAACACAAGUUCCCUAAAGCAGUAACUAUAGAAGAAAGAAUUACCCUAAUUGUUUCAGGCCAAUUAAGGCCCAUCCUAGAGGUGGAAAUGGGGUCAGCAUACUCAGAAGCAAAGAAGUAGAGAGAGUUGGAUACCUGAAUAAAAUUGGGAAAAGUUACAAAGAGAGGAAUGGAUGCUGGAGAGGAACCACCAGUUUCUACUACGAUAACCUAUUUACUUCAUUUUAAACGGUGAUAUUUUAAACGUGGGAACAUUUUGCCUAGUGAGUUUUUUUCUUUGAGAAACGUAGCAGUAUCUUGUAACAAAGAAGAUAUGGGGACACUCUGUCAUCAAAAACUACUUUGGGGCCGGGCAUGGUGGCUCACACCUGUAAUCCCAGCACUUUGGGAGGCCAAGGUGGGUGGAUCACCUGAGGUCAGGAGUUCAAGACCAGCCUGGCCACCAUGGUGAAACCCCACCUCUACUAAAAAUUACAAAAAUUAGCUGGGCGUGGUGGUACAUGACUGUAAUCUCAGCUACUUGGGAGGCUGAAGCAGGAGAAUUGCUUGAACCCGGGAAUCAGAAGCUGCAGUGAGCCGGGAUCACACCACUGCACUCCAGCCUGGGUGACAGAGCAAGGCUCUGUCUCAAUAACAACAACAAAAAAACAGAAACAAACAAAACAAAACAAACUACUGUUGGAGGUAGGAACUGGCCCAGGGGCUGUAUUCCCAGAACACGAUUCCCUUUUCCCCACUGCAAACAAGAUAGUCUACAGCAGCCUCACAACUUAAUUGUCUCACACAGGACUAUUCCUACUGUUAAGAGAUCACAGCUAAGGCUUGGGCACCUUGACCUGCUGUAGAAGCUCAGUUAAUGUACUUUUCAUCAUCUGGGCCCUGGUAUUCCCCUGUAAAUACUGAAGUAGACCCAGUGACCUAGUGCCCAAGACACAAAAUAUUCAGCCUCCGUAACAUUUGUCUAAUGACAUGGUUCUAGCUUUGCUCACUCCCAUUAAUUUCAAGUGAGUACUGGCUAGGCAGUCUAUAGUGACUUGAUUACACUGUCUUUCUUGUCCUGUGCUGUCCUGAGAAUCCUGGAUUUGAAGCAGCCUAUGAAUAAGGUUUGAAAAAUAUUUAUCCAACUAUGCCGACAUAUGAUGUUCUAGCACUGCAUCUGUCAUCUAUCACCCGCACCUUAAUAAAUGAUAAUUACUUGUGCAAACAUGAUGUAUUAAUCACUUAUUAACUUGGUUGCUUACUUGACAGACACUGCUAGGUGGUUUGCCUAUGCUGUACUUCGACAGAUCCUGGGAAAGAACAGCCUGGCUCAUUAUGCCCUGGAGGCAGGAGCAGAGAUUUCAGACUUCUGAUUUCUGUGAGCCAUUCCACACUUUCCUCUCGGUUAGGGGAGGGACAGCAAUAACCAGAGGAUGAAGGUGGAACCUUUGCAGUGCACACCUAGGCCAGUGCAGUGGCUUAUGCCUGUAAUCCCAGCACUUUGGGAGGCUGAGGCGGGUGGAUCACUUGAAGUCAGGAGUUUAAGACCAGCCUGACCAAUAUGGCGAAACCCUGUUUCUACUACAAAUACAAAUAUUCGCUGGGCAUGGCAAUGCAUGCCUGUAGUCCCAGCUACUUGGGAGGCUGAGGCCUGAGAAUUGCUUGAACCCAGGAGGCAGAGGUUGCAGUGAGCCAAGAUCAUGCCACUGCAUUCCAGCCUGGGCGACAGAGAUUCCAUCUUGAAAAAUAAAGUUCCAAAUACCUAAAUGCUCAAACUUUAGGAGGCAGCUCUCUGGGCUGUGGGCUGUCAGCAUCCCCCUCCUAGAUUCCAGGGAUUUGGUUACAUAGUUCUUUAGCUGUAAUGCAGAGUAUAAAUUUUAGAACCCACAUGGCCCCAAAUUCAAAUUGUUUUAAUGCAUGUAACUAGUGACUAAAAACUUAGAAUUUCAAUUUACAUCCAAGAGGUGGCACCAUAACACAACAGCAAAAAGCCACACAAACUGAAACUCGUUUCCUUUUGUAGUGAACAGCACUAUUAGGUAGUCUGCAGUGCCUGACUACGGGCUCACAUGCUGUGAUCCUUCUCGUUUUCUCAGAGCCAUUCCUUAAGCUUAGUCCCCUUGUAUCUUAAAUUUAGCUCAGGUCGGAGUGUUGUUAACUUGGGGCCAGCUGGGUUCGUGAGAGUCUCAGCCCAUUGCCAUGGUGGAGUCAGCAUGGUCUUGAGUUCCUUCCUUAACUCUGCAGGUUUCAGAAAUCCACGUAGCCAGUGUUUCUGAAAAUGGAUCUAGGCUGGGCAAUUGGCAAGGAGCUAAUUUCUUAUCAAGAUGCCAGCUUAUUAACUUGAGUGAAGAACACAACUGCCAAAUAGACUGUAUAGUGGGAUCUGCUAGUGAGAACAUUCUGUCCCUUUGGGAAAUCUCUUUAAGAGAAUCAUCAUUUGAAGGCUGCUUGGAGAGCCUGGAAUCAGAGCCAGGGAAAUUAGGGGCCAGGGUAAGGGAGCUAUGACCAUCUAUAGCUCCCAUUUCUGCUGCAGGGAUGGACCUAUGGUAUCAGCCAGCCACAGAAGGUCUUUUGGGACAACACUGGAGAUAAUGAUCCUUCAUAGUACAGGAACUCCCUUUUUCUAGGUUGCAGGAAGACCACCUAUUUCUACCCACAUAGGCAUUCCUCAGACAAUCCUCAUAAUUUAGUUAUUAAGGGUUUUUGCAUUUUAUAAUCCUGUCUGCCUCAGGGUCCAUCGGUCCCCUAGAUAGAGUUUGGGGAGGGAAGAAUCCCCAAACUUUGCAGCCACAAGUUACGUACUCCCUGGUCAUUUCUACAGAAAACUAAUCUGUGAUGUGUUUUUACUAUCGCAGUGACGUUCAAACUGUUUCAAAGCCUUAGGUUUCCCCAGAGAUGCCUAGGGGGAUUGGGGCACUGUGGACAAUAAGGGAGUGAGUCAAGUCAACAGAAAUGCUAGCUAGCCUUUAGUUCUCUUCUACAGCCGUACUGGGUGGCAUGUACACGUGAUAGCUGCUCACACCACAUGUGGCUAUUGAGCACUUGAAAUGUGGCUAACAUAAUUUAAAAGUAAAAGGUAAGGCUGGCCAUGUUGGCUCACGCUUGUAAUCCCAGCACUUUGGGAAGCUGAGGUAGGAGGAUAGUUUGUGGCCAGGAGUUUGAGACCAGCUUGGGCGACGUGGUAAGACCCCAUUUCUCCAAAAAAAAUUAAAAAAAUUAACUAGGCAUGGUGGUGUGUGCCUGUAGUCUCAGCUACUUGCGAGGCUGAGGCAGGAGGAUCACUUGAGCUCAGGAGUUCGACGUAGUGAGCCAUGAUUGCGCCACUGCACUCCAGCUUGGGUGAGAGGGCAAGACGCUGUCUCAAAUAAAUAAAAAUGAGCCCCCUCCCCCUCCCCCUCCCCCUCUCCCUCACCCUCUCCCUCUCCCCACGGUCUCCCUCUGAUGCCAAGCCAAAGCUGGACUGUACUGCUGCCAUCUCGGCUCACUGCAACCUCCCUGCCUGAUUCUCCUGCCUCAGCCUGCCCAGUGCCUGUGAUUGCAGGCGCGCGCCGCCACGCCUGACUGGUUUUGGUGGAGACGGGGUUUCGCUGUGUUGGCCGGGCCGGUCUCCAGCCCCUAACCACGAGUGAUCCGCCAACCUCGGCCUCCCGAGGUGCCGGGAUUGCAGACGGAGUCUCGUUCACUCAGUGCUCAAUGGUGCCCAGGCUGGAGUGCAGUGGCGUGAUCUCGGCUCACUACAACCUACACCUCCCAGCCGCCUGCCUUGGCCUCCCAAAGUGCCGAGAUUGCAGCCUCUGCCCGGCCGCCACCCCGUCUGGGAAGUGAGGAGUGUCUCUGCCUGGCCGCCCAUCGUCUGGGAUGUGAGGAGCCCCUCUGCCUGGCUGCCCAGUCUGGAAAGUGAGGAGCGUCUCCGCCCGGCCGCCAUCCCAUCUAGGAAGUGAGGAGCGCCUCUUCCCAGCCGCCAUCACAUCUAGGAAGUGAGGAGCGUCUCUGCCCGGCCGCCCAUCAUCUGAGAUGUGGGGAGCGCCUCUGCCCCGCCGCCCCAUCUGGGAUGUGAGGAGCGCCUCUGCCCGGCCGAGACCCCGUCUGGGAGGUGAGGAGCGUCUCUGCCCGGCCGCCCCGUCUGAGAAGUGAGGAGACCCUCUGCCUGGCAACCACCCCGUCUGAGAAGUGAGGAGCCCCUCCGCCCGGCAGCUGCCCCAUCUGAGAAGUGAGGAGCCUCUCCGCCCGGCAGCCACCCCAUCUGGGAAGUGAGGAGCGUCUCCGCCCGGCAGCCACCCCGUCCGGGAGGGAGGUGGGGGGGGGUCAGUCCCCCGCCCGGCCAGCCACCCCAUCCGGGAGGGAGGUGGGGGGGUCAGCCCCCCGCCUGGCCAGCCGUGCCGUCCGGGAGGGAGGUGGGGGGUCAGCCCCCCGCCCGGCCAGCCGCCCCGUCCGGGAGGUGAGGGGCGCCUCUGCCCGGCCGCCCCUACUGGGAAGUGAGGAGCCCCUCAGCCCGGCCAGCCACCCCGUCCGGGAGGGAGAUGGGGGGUCAGCCGCCCCGUCCGGGAGGGAGGUGGGGGGGUCAGCCCCCCGCCUGGCCAGCCGCCCCGUCCGGGAGGGAGGUGGGGGGGUCAGCCCUCCGCCCGGCCAGCCGCCCCGUCUGGGAGGUGAGGGGCGCCUCUGCCCGGCCGCCCCUACUGGGAAGUGAGGAGCCCCUCUGCCCGGCCAGCCGCCCCGUCCGGGAGGGAGGUGGGGGGGGGUCAGCCCCCCUGCCCUGCCAGCCGCCCCGUCUGGGAGGUGAGGGGCGCCUCUGCCCGGCCGCCCCUACUGGGAAGUGAGGAGCCCCUCUGCCCGGCCACCACCCCGUCUGGGAGGUGUGCCCAACAGCUCAUUGAGAACGGGCCAGGAUGACAAUGGCGGCUUUGUGGAAUAGAAAGGCGGGAAAGGUGGGGAAAAGAUUGAGAGAUCGGAUGGUUGCUGUGUCUGUGUGGAAAGAAGUAGACAUGGGAGACUUUUCAUUUUGUUCUGCACUAAGAAAAAUUCCUCUGCCUUGGGAUCCUGUUGAUCUGUGACCUUGCCCCCAACCCUGUGCUCUCUGAAACAUGCGCUGUGUCCACUCAGGGUUAAAUGGAUUAAGGGCGGUGCAAGAUGUGCUUUGUUAAACAGAUGCUUGAAGGCAGCAUGCUCGUUAAGAGUCAUCACCACUCCCUAAUCUCAAGUAAUCAGGGACACAAACACUGCGGAAGGCCGCAGGGUCCUCUGCCUAGGAAAACCAGAGACCUUUGUUCACUUGUUUAUCUGCUGACCUUCCCUGCCAAAUCCCCCUCUGUGAGAAACACCCAAGAAUUAUCAAUAAAAAAAUAAAUUAAAAAAAAAUAAAAAUAAAUAAAUAAAAAUGAAAAACAAAAGCAUAAUAGAAAUAAAGACCAUGUUGGAAACAGUGCAACAGAGAAGAGGCUGAAAACGGUAUGAAAUUUAGAAGGCAAGAUAGAGAACAGUGAAUAAAGACAGGAAAAUAACAGCUAUAGAAGUCAGUUAAAAAUAAUAAUAAUAAUUAUUAUUAUUAUUAUUAUUAUUUGAGACGAAGUUUCGCUCUUGUUGCCUAGGCUGGAGUGCAGUGGUUCAAUCUUGGCUCACUGCAACCUCCGCCUCCCAGGUUCAAGCGAUUCUCCUGCCUCAGCCUUCCAAGUAGCUGGGAUUACAGGCCUGAGCCACCAUGCCUGGCUAAAUUUUUUUCUUGUUGUUGUAUUUUUAGUAGAGACGGGGUUUCACCAUGUUGGCCAGGCUGGUCUCAGACUCCUGACCUCAGGCGAUCCAUCCGCCUUGGCCUCCCAAAUUACUGGGAUUACAGGCGUGAACCACUGCAUCCAGCCAAAAUUAUUCAUUUUUGUAUUGUUUCACUUUUUAUAUUUUUUAUUUUAUUUUAUUAUUUUAUUUUAUUUUAAUUUUAUUUUGAGACGGAGUCUCACUCUGUCACCCAGGCUGGAGUGCAGUGUCGCAGUCUCGGCCUACUGCAAGUUCUGCGUCCUGGGUUCACGCCAUUCUCCUGCCUCAGCCUCCUGAGUAGCUGGGACUGCAGGUGCCCGCCACCACGCCCGGCUAAUUUCUUUUUGUAUUUUUAGUAGAGACGGGGUUUCACCGUGUUAGCCAGAAUGGUCUCGAUCUCCUGACCUCGUGAUCCGCCUGCCUCGGCCUCCCAAAGUACUGGGAUUACAGGCGUGAGCCACCGCGCCAGCUUUAUUAUUUUGUAAACACACAAGUUGAGGAAAUUUUAAAAUGAGAAAAAUACACACACAAACAACAAAGCUCUAGCCAUUAGCAAUUAGAACAGCUUUAUUUACCUAAUUCAGACAAAGAGACUGGAGAUUCUUUAGGGAGUUAAAGGCACGAGCAGUGGAAAAAAACCAUGAGAUCAUCAUCACAUCAUCCCCUGAAGCUGUCUCAGGAGGAGUCACUGAAACCCAGAGAAAAUCUAACUGGUAAUUAAUACAUAGGGCUCUCGUGUCCCUGAGGGAAAGGAGUGAAAACACCAACUGAAUUAGCCCAUACAUGGGGCUGUCUGUGCCCUUUAGGGAGAGGAGUGAAAACAACUGAAAUCAGCCCAUCAGCCCAUGAAGACACUGGUGAAAAUUAUGCGACUUGUCCUUCUUGCACCUAAGCAGCCCACAGAUAACUCACUCUUAUAUACGAACCUGACUGACUGGGUAGCCAUUAUGUGCCUAGCUUAGUGCUGCAUGCUUUAUGCUCUCUCUUAAUCCUGCAAUGGGGCAGUCGAAUCACAUAUUAGCUGUUUUUGUUGCCUGUUUGUUUUUGAGACGGAGUCUCGCUCGGUCACCCAGGCUGGAGUGCAGUGGUGCAAUCUUGGCUCACUGCAACCUCCGCCUCCUGGGUUCAAGCGAUUCUCCUGCCUCAGCCUCCGGAGUAGCUGGGAUUACAGUCAUGUACCACCACACCCAGCUAAUUUUUGUAUUUUUAGUAGAGAUGGGGUUUUGCCAUGUUGGCCAGGCUGGUCUGGAACUCCUGACCUCAGGUGAUCCUUCCACCUUGGCCUCCCAAAGUGAUGGGAUUACAGGCGUGAGCCACCGUGCCUGGCCAGCUGUUCUGACUGAAGACUUGUCUUCUUCGUUAACCUGCUCCUCCUGUUUCAUCCUGCAAAUGUUUAAAUCUGAGGGGUAUUAUCCACAGCUCAUCUCCACUUUUCUAAUCUGACAGCACUGAUAAUUGAAUUCCUCAGAAGCAAGAUGUUUCUCUGGCACCCAGAGGCCUCAGCAGUGUCACGACAGCUGAAGUGUCACUUAUUCCUCAUCCUGGGCACACCAUGAUGGAGUGCAGCCCCACUGAUUGGGACCCAUGCAGCCAGCCUGGCCCAGGGCCACUCUCUCUCCCAGAAUGUGCACAAGUCAAGGGAUCUCUACUUCCAUCCUUAUUUUCCUCAAAAGCUGGUGCCAGCAGUAAUCAACCAGACUUCUAGAAAAGAGGAGAUAAUCUGCUCUCAAGGCUGCUGUGGGCUCCAGUGUUGUAAUCUACUACUUGAAUCUAGUUGUUUAUUUCAUUCUAUAAUAAUUUAAUACAGCAGAUGUCAGGAGAAAUCUUUGUUUAGAUAUUAUGUCAUAUCUGGAUAUAUCUGAAUCCUGAAUGAUUAAUCUAAAUAUUAACAAUAUUCACUUCUGCCAAUGUCAAGAGUAUUUUCUGCUACUGGGCUUAAAUCAAUUUUAAAAUUUGAGAGUUUUAAAAGCAUAUCUUUCUGUGUUCAUAAAUAAACAGAACGAAGAUUCUUUGA